UUGAACAUCCUAGAAGGAACUAUGGCCCUGGCCUCCUACUCCUUGGCCCCCCUGAUGCCGCUUUCAAUGGGUCUCACCUUCCUGCUCAGCCCAGCCUCCCCCUUCCAGCCUGACCUGCCCCACAGUAGCAGCAGCAGGGAUAGACCUCCCUGCCCUCCUCUUCCUCCGUUUGUCUUAAGAGUUCAUAGUAGUAAUAGAGGGUGUUGACUGCACAUGGUCAGUCUCGUUGCUAUGGUGGAAGGCUGUCUUAACGUCUGAGUGGUUAAGGAUUGAGGAGGUGAUAUUUACUUACAUGCAGCCGGUUUCUCCUCUCGGCCCGCUGUUCCAUAGACACCCAUAAUGUCCUGAAACGCUGGCCCGAGGAGGGUCCCGGCUGUCUCCAUCUUUAUCCACACGGUCGGCCCCCCGCAGUGCCUGGUGUUUUGACUUCACAACCACAGUUGCGUAAAUGUCCCCAUAGCGUCUGGCUGAGGAGCCAUUUCAUCGUGGCCUCCUCCACUCACCUGCUCUUCCUUCACGCCCCAAGGCGCUGGCCUCUCUUUCCAGUGGCUCUUCCGGAUCCUGCAGCUUUUGGGUCAUGUGAGUUGCCUCAUGGCCCUAAAGUUCUCUCGGACUUGAGAGCUGUGAUUGUCUUUCUCUUUUUGUUCCAUCUCCAGAGAGACAGUGCUGCGAGGUCCCCGCCUCGUCCUCACCCCCGCUCCUGACCCCACAAGUAACUAAGCAAUUGUUUCUUAGGGUCUUGGCUGCCCUAUUUCCUAAAAUGUGCCUCCACUACUAUUAAUUGGUUUUUCCAUUUCCUUGUCAGCUACUCAGUGCACUUCUUGCACAGGCUUUUUUUUUUUUUUUUUUCUUUGAGACGGAGUCUUGCUUUAUCACCCAGGCUGGUGUGCAGUGGCGUGAUCUUGGCUCACUGCAACCUCCGCCUCCCGGGUUCAAGCAAUUCUCCUGCCUCAGCCUCCUGAGUAGCUGGGAUUACAGGCGCCUGCCACCUCGCCCAGCUAUUUUUGUAUAUUUAGCAGAGACAGAGUUUUACCAUGUUGGCCAGGCUGGUCUCAAACUCCCAACCUCAGGUGAUCUGCCUGCCUCGGCCUCCCAAAGUGCUGGGAUUACAGGCGUGAGCCACCAUACCCGGCCACGUUUGGUUUCACUUUAGCCUAGAAACCUGCUCGCGGCUGACUGGGGGGUGCUCUGUGGUCCCAUCUUCCUAACACAGCUCUGUCUUCUCUGUGGGGUGGCAGCUGCUGCGUUUGUUUGCCUGCUUUUGUGUGUCCAGGUCGACCCCACCUGGAUCCGAUCAUCCACAACCGCAGGUUGCUGGAACCUCCCAGUGCAGCCUGGCCUGGGGGCAGAGGCCGGGCCCAGCUGUCCCUCGGGGUUCACUGUGCUGACUCCCUGCUUCUGGGCCUGCCUUUCUCUUUCUUGGUUUUCUUUAUAAUUUUGUGGUUUGGAGAAGUCCUGCCUCCCGUCGUUUCCUGGGCCGGUCCCGGGAGGUAGCACGUUGAGGCCUUUCAUGUCUGAAAUGUCUGUCGCUUCCCUCCGCCGGAGGGGCAGCCUGGCCUCCGUGGUGUCACAGGUGCAGAGCCUGCCCUUGAACGUCCCUGCCGCUUUUGCGUGACUGAUCCUCUGUGUGCCGUCAGCUUUGCUUGAGGUUUUAGGGUCUUUGCUCCCUCCCAGCUGUACCUGGCUGUGCUGGGGGCCUUUUUAGGCUUUGGGCUUGUGUCCUUCAUCGUGGGGUCAUCCUCUCGUGCUCUUUGUUAACUUCCCCAUCAUCAUCCCUUUCUGUUGCUCCUGUUAAUCAGAUGUUGAUCCUCCCAGAUGAGGGCGUCUUUUUUUUUUUUUUGAGACAGUUUCACUCUUGUCGCCCAGGCUGGAGUGUAGUGGCGUGGUCUUGGCUCACUGCAACCUCUGUCUCCCAGGUUCAAGUGAUUUUCCUGUCUCAGCCUUCUGAGUAGCUGGGAUUACAGGUGCACACCACCACGCCCAGCUAAUUUUUUGUAUUUUUUUAGUAGAGAUGGGGUUUCACCAUGUUGGCCAGGCUGGUCUUGAACUCCUGACCUCGUGAUCCGCCUGCCUCGGCCUCCCAAAGUGCUGGGAUUACAGGCGUGAGCCACCGUGCGCAGCCCCUUGCUGGAUAUUUUCAUCCGUGUGGAAGGGGAUAAAGCGUGCCCCAUGGUCACACCACCCCCUCCCGUGGCCUGGCGUCCCCACCUUCGUCCUGACCUCUUCUGUCUCGUGGUCCCCAGGCUCCUGUGCUGCUGUGCCCCUCAGGGUCCUCCUGCCUCCCGAGCCUCCCUGCUCCACAUGGCCCCUGCCCAGCCCUCUCCAUCCCUCUUGAAGGACAGUGGACGCUGCUCCCUGCCUCUUCCUCAGAGUCCUGGGGUCACACCUCUACCUGCGCGGCUCUCGGGGGCCACCCCUCUCAGCCCCAUCCGGCUCCUGAGCAGCUUUGUCCCCAGAGGGCCCCGGGUCAUUCCUCUGACCAACCAGGCACGGCGCACCCUGCAUGCAAGCCUGGGCGGGUGCUGGGGACGGACGAGUGACGCAGCAGACACUGCCUCCCUGAAGGCAUGGCAAGGUGGGACGCUUGGCCGCCACCUGCAGGGGCCUCACCUGACCAGUCCCCAGCCUCAGGAGGCGGACCCCAGCAGCUGGAGCCCCAGCAGAGUUGGGGGGAUGGUGGCAUCUGUGUCCUGGGCUCCGGGGCCACCUCACUGUGAGGAGGAGGUGUGGGCGUUGUGGGAGGUCUCAUCUCGGGGCCAUGCUGAUCUGGGCUCUGAGAGCUGGUGUCCGCUGCUCCUCCCCUCCCAUUUCUCAACAGGAGGCCCCGAGUUCCUGAAGACGCCCCUGGGGGGCAGCUUCCUGGUGUACGAGUCCUUCCUCUACCGGCGGGAGAAGGCGGCCGGGGAGAAGGUGUAUUGGACCUGCCGGGACCAGGCCCGCAUGGGCUGCCGCAGCCGCGCCAUCACCCAGGGCCGGCGGGUCAUGGUCAUGCGCAGGCACUGCCACCCACCGGACCUGGGCGGCCUGGAGGCCCUGCGGCAGCGGGAGCACUUCCCCAACCUGGCGCAGUGGGACAGCCCAGAUCCUCUCCGGCCCCUGGAGUUCCUGAGGACUUCCCUGGGGGGCAGGUUCCUGGUGCACGAGUCCUUCCUCUACAGGAAGGAGAAGGCGGCUGGGGAGAAGGUGUACUGGAUGUGCCGGGACCAGGCUCGGCUGGGCUGCCGCAGCCGCGCCAUAACCCAGGGCCACCGCAUCAUGGUCAUGCGCAGCCACUGCCAUCAGCCUGACCUGGCAGGCCUGGAGGCCUUGAGGCAACGGGAGCGGCUCCCCACCACGGCCCAGCAGGAGGACCCAGAAAAGAUUCAAGUUCAGCUGUGCUUCAAGACGUGUUCUCCUGAAAGCCAGCAGAUUUAUGGGGACAUCAAAGACGUCAGACUGGAUGGCGAGUCCCAGUGAGGCGAUGUGGGCAGAGGAGCUCCGAGCCGCCCACCCAAGGUGGCUUCACAUCCACACAGGCACUUCCCAUCCACCUAGGUUUGGCUUAGCAGAAACUUCUUUUCAUUCUUCCAAAGCAUCGAUGGUCUUCGCGUCUCCUCAGGAGGUCUCCCAGGAGGAAUUCUUGGAUGGUGUCCUCAUGUCGGCGGAGAACAGUGCUCAGAGCUGGCGCUUGCAGACGCAGCUGUCGUGGGGCAGGGCGGUGGCGCCUUCCUGACCUUUGGAAGACAUGACAAAGCUGCCUGGACACGGACGCCCCUGCUGUACGGCCACAGCACCCCUGGGUUUGCAGAGCACGCAGCCUUCCUAGGGCUUUCCACCUGGCGAGGCCCCGCUCUGCUCAGCACGGUGCAAAGUGAAUGCUGCUGUCUUGGAGCCUGGGCACGUUUGGGGAAGUUCCUGCUUCAAACUGAGCUGCCCCGCAUAGGCCAGGUCAACCCACACCAAUCUCUUCUGGACAGGUGCUGGGUAGGCCUUCCUGGUCUCUGGCCGCCUGCUGCCAGGGUGUGGCCAUCCCCAGCAACCGGAGCUGGCCAAACCAGAGGCCUCGCUCCGCACUCCACACUUUCCUUUCUGUGCUCCUUCCAAGUUAAAUUAAACCCCCUCUCCACGAUUCCCACGGCAGGCGUCAUUCCCGAGAUGGGAGCCAGUCCAGGGGUCAGCAGGAGCCAGCGCUGGGCACACGUGCCCUGGCUGAGGCCAGCGGCAUCCUGGGUGGCCCAGGUCCAUCCUGGGCAGCAAAGGCGUGUCCCCUUCUGUCAGACAGCUUCACAGAGUGUGGCUUCACCAGUCAGAGGGAGCAGUCCGGAGAGGCAAGAUGACCCCACCGGGACUGCAGAGCCUCCUCCUUACUAACAAGGACCUGUCCGCAGCCGCGAGGUCCUUCACUCCCACCCUGUAAUUGUGGGGGGAGUGCCAGCAACAGGCCUGUCCCCUGGCAAGUUGGCCACGGAACCCACCAUGCACUGCAAGGCUGUGACAGCCUGGGCACCCCUGCUUCUCCUCUGCUUGUACGGUUCCCCCAAUAAAUCCUAUUUUCCAUCUCACCGUGUGGAGCUGGUACUUGUUCACAUCCCUCUUGCAGCAACAGUUGGCCGCCGUGAAACCACACUCCGUCACAUCUCCAUGCCAGUGCCCAGGGGGAGACCCCUCCCCAUGCCUGGGCUGUUACAGUCACCUGGCCCAGACGUAACCUGGACCAAGAGUGGACGGAGACACCUGGGGUUGGGGCCUCUGGAAGGGCUGCUGGGGGGCCAGCUGCAGCCUGUGGCCUCUCCCAGGCCCGGAUAUGGCAGGACAUUUGCGUCGUGUUGCUGGAAGAGGCAGGAUGCUCUGUUCUCGCCAUUAGCCUGCGUUACGCCUAGACUCAUCUGCAUAAGCCUGGGCAAGUGGCACCCCUGGGCCAAGGGCAGACUUGCCCACCCGUCCAUCCUUUGCCUAUGGCAGAGGACACACAACACAGUGGCUGCGCUUUGGGCACUGUUCUCGGCCCUGAAGCAUCCUGCCCCGAGGCUGACCUAACUGCCCCCAGCUGGACUCAUGGCCAAGGCUACAGACCCAGUACUCCAAUCCCGACUCCCACUGUGUGGUCCAAAUGUGUACGCCCACAGGAGGCAGCCAUGCCCGAGGAAGGUACUUGCUGAAAGAUGGUCCAGUUCAUGCCGCCACCAGCUGGACCUCUGAUCAGGCCCCCUGCAGAAGGGGAAGCUCUCCACAUGCCCAAGAUACGAGAGAAACGCCCGGGUCACAGCAGCCUGAGUCACUGCAGCCUCUGCUACCUGCCAAGCCUGCGCCCUCCACCUGUGGGCUCCUUGCCUCUGUGAUGGGGCCUCCACGGCCAGCAUCUUCCCGCCAUGGUCACAUGAUGCCAUGCCCUGCUCUGGGCACCCCUAAGCGGGUAUGAGGCGAAUCAGAGGAAGAAUAUCGGCUUCUCUUCCCUUUUGGAUAUUUGCGUCAUUGACCGGGACUGGCCCACUCUUCCUCUGCCUCACGCCUGCUUUGACCUUAGAAGACAGACGGCAGCUCGCGUUGCUGGGCUGAGAUUCUCCAAUGGACGUGAAUUUAGAUGAUGCUGUUGCCUUGGGUGGCUUCAUGGCCACCAACCCGCACCCUGGUGGCCACUCAGCCAUGACAAGGGCCUGACAGCCACUAAGUGAGCUUCAGAGCCUUCCCCUUGCAAAGUUCCAGGGCCACCAGAUGUCGCCUGCCCAGUCACUGUCACAGAGUUAAAGCGUGCGGGUGAACGCUGGCCGCGGAGCGUGCAGCCCGGCAGCAGCUCAGCGGGGCAGCUCCUGCUUCCAGCCCUGCCUCUGCUGGUGCUUCGCCCACAAACCCUGCUGUAUGACAUUUGCACCACAUGGUGUGUGUCCGUGCCCUUUGACAUGACAGUGCCAACAACAUCUCAUGAAAUUUAAAAUAAAUCCCCAAGGCAUCAGAAACGUA